CCCCGCGCUGUCUCGGCGGCCCAGGGUGAGUCGGCCGCGGCCGCGGGGCGGGGACUGGGAGGGGCGCGGUCCUCCGAGCCCGGCCUGGUGGAGGCUGUAGCCCCCGCAGUGGGCGCGCGGAGCUCGGCAGGGAGCGGACCCGCAGCCGUCACUGUCGCCUCCGCUCGCCUUGGGUUCCGAACCCUUAUCGGGGCGAAGGGCCCUGCGCCCCGGUCCAUGCUGGCUGUGGUCGGGGGCGUGCGGCCGGGCCCCCGAGACCCGCUCCGCCGAGCCGGACGGUUGCGCAGAGAUGAGGCUGCAGGCGGGGAGGCCUGGCGAGGUGGGGCUGCUCCGGGGAGGACCAGGCUCUGCCCCUCGCUUCCGUCCGAUGGCGGGCUCUUCCCGGCAGCCUCGCUCCCCGGCGGACGCCGUUUCCCGCAGCGUUCAUUUACCCUGCGCAGUUUUGCCCCCUCCCCGGGUUGGGGCAUUUAUUGGACCAACAGUCAUUUCGUAAAUAGCUGUUGGGUAUUUAACUGUGAGCGUUCCGGUGCUGGGGACCCCGCAGUGAGCGAACAGCCCGCCUCGCCUCCAGGAGCAUGAAUUGUAAUAGAGAAUUCACUGUCUGUAGCAUCUGCUCCUCCACAGAGGGACCCUGGAAUGGCGAUGGCACUCCCGAUGCCUGGACCUCAGGAGGCGGUUGUGUUCGAGGAUGUGGCUGUGUACUUCACAAGGAUAGAGUGGAGUUGCCUGGCCCCCGACCAGCAGGCACUCUACAGGGACGUGAUGCUGGAGAACUAUGGGAACCUGGCCUCACUAGGCUUUCUUGUUGCCAAACCAGCACUGAUCUCCCUAUUGGAGCAAGGAGAGGAGCCGGGGGCCUUGAUUCUGCAGGUGGCUGAACAGAGCGUGGCCAAAGCCAGCCUGUGCACAGAGGACCCUAAUACACUGCCCAGCAGAAGCCAGGAAGGAAGCCCUGCCAGCUCAGAAGGUGGGCCAGGAGAGAAGGGUGUGGCCGGAAGGGUAGCCGGUGGGGGUGCUGCAUCCUCUUGGCCCCACGGGGAGCACCCUGUCACCCCUAACAGAUGAAGAGAAGGUGAGGGGGGAUUGAGUUACCUGCCCACUGGUGUGUCAAACUCCAUGAUGGGGGUGGGAACAUGCAGACCUGGCCCCUCCAAGGCCCACUGCUCCCCGGGCUGUGCGCCCCACAGUCUGUGCCAGGGGCUGCAGAAAGAGCCAUGGGAAGCCUGGCCCUGGUAGGGCACCAAGAUGGGGAGGGCUGGAUCCACCCUCCAGAGAACAAGAAUCCUGGGCAGUAGCCGGGACAUGGUGGGGGAGGCUGAAGGGUUGUCCCUGAGCAUCCCCAACAUGGAGCUCGGAAGUCUGGGCCAUGGGCAGGAAAGCACGAAGGUCAGGGCCAGCCUGGGGAACCAAGAGCUGUGCCACGAUCCCUUCCACCUGGGGCAGCUGCCCACAUGCCCGCCACUGGGUUCCAUCACCUGAGACUCCUGGCAGGUGCCUCUCUGAGUCUUUGUCCUGUGCUGGAAACUGGGAUGUGCAGCACACAUCUUCACACCCACAGCACGGACAGCGGGAAUAACACUUCCUUUGGGGAUCCAGGGUUUCUGGUGUCUCCAGAUUUUUCAGGCGCCACCAUGUUCCUCUCAUCCAGACGUCAGCACCCAAGGUGGAAGCAGGUCAUGGCAUGCCCGGCCCAGCUGCAGUCCGAGUGCAGAUCCCAUGGCGAGCGUGGGAUCCAGCCCAAAGCACAAGCCACGCACAGCCCGCCAGGUUGAGUGGGCAGGUACCUCCAACAGCCAGCCCAGGUUGAGUGGGCAGGUACCUCCAACAGCCUGGAGCCGUGAGGCCUUGCGCAGGGGCGUUGCCGGCCGUGGAGGUCUCUGGCUGGCAAAGUGGCACCGAAAGAGUCCUGUGUCAUAACCAGACUCACUUGUAGCUUCUGUUGCUCUCCCUAGCUAUUUGCAAAGCAUCCAGGAUAGGUUCAUCUAAAGACAUUCUGACUCAUCUUGGACACGAUCCACUUACUCUGUGGACCCUGUUCACAGAACCUGGAGUCCCUGCUCACCUUCCCCAACCCCUUAUUGCUGGGUCAUGUUCACAAGUUUCUGUCUCUUUUUGUUCCCAGUCCCGGUACCAGCUCAGGUCCAAUCAGCUUCUGAACCUCUACUGUGCAGCGCCUGAGACAGGGUGGGAGAGACACCGACAGUAAAGCUCAGCCAGGUGCAGACUGCAGCCUGGAAGCAAAGGCUGAGACAGGGUGGGAGAGACACCGACAGUAAAGCUCAGCCAGGUGCAGACUGCAGCCUGGAAGCAAAGGCUGAGACAGGGUGGGAGAGACACCGACAGUAAAGCUCAGCCAGGUGCAGACUGCAGCCUGGAAGCAAAGGCUGAGACAGGGUGGGAGAGACACGGACAGUAAAGCUCAGCCAGGUGCAGACUGCAGAAUGGAAGCAAAGGCUGAGACAGAGUGGGAGAGACACCGACAGUAAAGCUCAGCCAGGUGCAGACUGCAGCGUGGAAGCAAAGGCUGAGACAGGGUGGGAGAGACACGGACAGUACGCUCAGCCAGGUGCAGACUGCAGCCUGGAAGCAAAGGCUGAGACAGGGUGGGAGAGACACGGACAGUAAAGCUCAGCCAGGUGCAGACUGCAGAAUGGAAGCAAAGGCUGAGACAGGGUGGGAGAGACACGGACAGUAAAGCUCAGCCAGGUGCAGACUGCAGCCUGGAAGCAAAGGCUGAGACAGGGUGGGAGAGACACGGACAGUAAAGCUCAGCCAGGUGCAGACUGCAGAAUGGAAGCAAAGGCUGAGACAGAGUGGGAGAGACACCGACAGUAAAGCUCAGCCAGGUGCAGACUGCAGAAUGGAAGCAAAGGCUGAGACAGGGUGGGAGAGACACCGACAGUAAAGCUCAGCCAGGUGCAGACUGCAGCCUGGAAGCAAAGGCUGAGACAGGGUGGGAGAGACACUGACAGUAAAGCUCAGCCAGGUGCAGACUGCAGAAUGGAAGCAAAGGCUGAGACAGGGUGGGAGAGACAGGGACAAUAAAGCUCAGCCAGGUGCAGACUGCAGAAUGGAAGCAAAGGCUGAGACAGGGUGGGAGAGACACGGACAGUAAAGCUCAGCCAGGUGCAGACUGCAGCCUGGAAGCAAAGGCUGAGACAGGGUGGGAGAGACAGGGACAAUAAAGCUCAGCCAGGUGCAGACUGCAGAAUGGAAGCAAAGGCUGAGACAGGGUGGGAGAGACACGGACAGUAAAGCUCAGCCAGGUGCAGACUGCAGAAUGGAAGCAAAGGCUGAGACAGGGUGGGAGAGAGACGGACAGUAAAGCUCAGCCAGGUGCAGACUGCAGCCUGGAAGCAAGGGCAGUGCCAUCCUCUUUCGGGGCAUUUCUGGUCACUUCAGUCUGCUGGGGGGAUUCCGUGUCUCACCAGGAGACUCAGGCAUGGACCUGGGUUGCCACUUUCUUCCUGUUACAUGGAUCUCUCUACCAUGCCCCAGACCCAACACCUCAGCCUUCUCAAAGCUGCACUGCAGAAGUUCUAGCCAGAGCAGCCUGGUAAGAGAAAGACGUAAAGAGCAUCCAAAUACUUCCUUCCAAAUGAGGAAGCCAAAUGGUCCUUGUUUGCAUUCAACGUGAUCUUAUAUAUAGAAAACCCUAAAAGCUUUAUCAAAACAUUCUUAGAACAAACAAAUUCAGUAAAGUUGCAGGAUACAAAAUUAACAUACAAAACCCAGUAACAUUUCUACAUACCAAACUACCAAAAAAAACCAGGAAAGCAAUUCCAUUUACAAUAGCUACCAAAACCAAAAAACAAACCUAGGAAUAAAUUUAACCAAUGAGGCUGGG